AACAAUGGGACUUCCACAGCAAUGGGAUCUGCUUCCUCUUUCAGUGUGUGCCUUUUCUAUGAGCAAGAGACUCCUAGGAAAGCAGCAGCCCAUUAGGAAAACGUGUGGGAACUCACUCGCAGACUGGACUCUGAAAUGGGCAUGUACAGAGACGAAGAGACCCCAACAUGCUUCAGGCUUUGAGUGGAGAGGACACAGCCUCUGCUGGGACAGGGAACAGAGGGAUGUGGAGUCCCCGAAGAUGCUUUUGGACAAUGGUCUGAGGUUGGGACAGUGGCAGGAGAUACCAUUCACCCAGGAUCUCCAGGACAAGAGAUCAGCCUGGCAGUUACAUGUGUUUUUUUUCAAACUGGUUGCCAGGUUGGCAUGAACGAUGACAUCAGAGAUUCCGACCUUCCUGAUUGGAGGGACCGGACUCCGUGGUGCCUGGAGAUCAGUUGGACAACAGUAUCUUCUCAGAGCUGUUCUCCACUCCUGACUUCUCCUAGGCUUGAGAAUUGAUAACAUACUCUUCUGGAUCCUAGCAGUGUCCAGAAGAAGGCCAUGGACAGAACGGAGACUAGGUUCCGUAAGAGGGGACAGAUUAAGGGAAAGAUCACGACCAGCCGUCAACCGCACCCCCAGAAUGAGCAGAGUCCCCAGCGGAGCACCUCGGGGUACUCCCUCCAGGAGGUGGUGGAUGAUGAAGUGUUGGGAUCAUCAGCCCCUGGGGUAGAUCCCAGCCCCCCAUGUAGGUCCCUUGGCUGGAAAAGGAAGAAGGAGUGGUCAGAUGAAUCUGAGGAGGAGCCGGAGAAGGAGCUCGCCCCUGAGCCUGAGGAGACCUGGGUAGUGGAGAUGCUGUGUGGGCUCAAGAUGAAGCUGAAGCAACAGCGAGUGUCACCCAUCCUCCCUGAGCACCACAAGGACUUCAACAGUCAGCUUGCCCCUGGGGUAGAUCCCAGCCCCCCGCAUAGGUCCUUUUGCUGGAAAAGGAAGAGGGAGUGGUGGGACGAAUCUGAGGAGUCGUUGGAGGAGGAGCCACGGAAGGUGCUCGCCCCUGAGCCUGAGGAGAUCUGGGUGGCGGAGAUGCUGUGUGGCCUCAAGAUGAAGCUGAAGCGACGGCGAGUGUCGCUCGUGCUCCCUGAGCACCACGAGGCCUUCAACAGGCUGCUUGAGGAUCCUGUCAUUAAAAGAUUCCUGGCCUGGGACAAAGAUCUGAGGGUGUCGGACAAGUAUCUCCUGGCUAUGGUCAUAGCGUAUUUCAGCCGGGCCGGCCUCCCCUCCUGGCAAUACCAACGCAUUCAUUUCUUCCUGGCUCUCUACCUGGCCAAUGACAUGGAGGAGGACGACGAGGACCCCAAACAAAACAUCUUCUACUUCCUGUAUGGGAAGACCCGCUCUCGCAUACCCUUGGUCCGUAACCGUCGGUUCCAGCUAUGCCGUUGCUUGAACCCGAGGGCCAGGAAGAACCGCUCUCAGAUAGCCCUGUUCCAGAAACUUCGGUUCCAGUUCUUCUGUUCCAUGAGCGGCAGGGCUUGGGUUUCCCGGGAGGAGUUGGAGGAGAUCCAGGCUUAUGACCCAGAGCACUGGGUGUGGGCGCGAGAUCGCGCUCGCCUUUCCUAGAGCUCCAGGGACCGUGGAGGCCUGAGGUCAUCGGCCUGAGAGAAGAACACCGGACCCAGGGGAGAUGUGGAUUUUCAGCAGGAACUUUAUUCCAAUGCUAAUGGCAGACAACAGGAAAGAGGAGAGGAACCAUUUGUGCAGAUCAUCUAGAAGAACCUGGACCAUUCUUGAUGGAGCUGAAUACAGUGAUCACGUUGUCCUCCUGGGAGCAGGGGUGGGGGGAGGGGGGUGGGGUCCUUCUAGGAGUCCUUGGAGAAAAGUAAGAAACCAGGAGUGUUUCCAGUUCCACCCUUUCCUGCGGCACCACCACCCUUUCUAUAUUGCUGAAUUCCAACCUCCCUGGGCCGGAACCUGGAGGUCCUGUUUCUUACAGACUUGGUUGCCACAGUCCAGGAGCAUUUGAAGGCACAAUGCAGGGGCUCAGAUUGGCACAGAAUUCUUUUGUGAAAUAUCAGUGCCACAGAUUGUAACAGAUAGCUUCAUGCACACUCUGCAUUUUAUUGGUUUGUUUGGAAAUGUUGGCCAUUGAAUUAUUCAUAGAUUUAUUUCAAAUAGUUUGGAAAUUGUUGUACUUUUGAAAACAUGCUGUUCCUGUAGUUUUUUGAUGAGAGUUAUAGUUGUUAUAUAUACAUAAAGAUAAUUUUCUUUUCAUUUUUAAGAGACAAUUCUUUUUAUCCUAAAUAUUUUAUUAUCUUUAAAUUUCUUUCUGUAUUAUUAUAUGCGCUCCUGAAGCGAGCACUCUUUUUAUCUAUGAUACUUCCAUAAAAAUCUCUUCUAUUUAUAGCUAUUGGUAGUUCCCCACCACAAAAAAACAUAAUUCUGGUGAUAGAAAUUUUUAUUUGCUGUUUAGGUUUGUGACUGAAUUGUGAGAAUUCAGUUGUGAUUUUUAACAUGUCUCAGAUAUAUAUACUAACACGUCUAAUACAUACUAUCUAAUUUAUUGGUUUAUUUUGAAAAACAUGGGUAUAGAAUUAUUUAAAUAUUAUUUUAUUUAUUGAAAUAUUUAUUAAAUAUAUUUAUUUAUUUAAAUAUUAUUAUUACUUUAAAUAUUAUUUUAAAUAUUUUGGAAAUACUGGUAUUUUUGAAUAGAUGCUGUUUCUAUAAAGCUGUGUGAUGGGUGUUAUAACUGUUAUAUACACAUACAUAUAAUUUUGUUUUCCUUUUUAAGAGAGGAUUCUUUUCAUCCUAAAUCUUUUACCUUUCAAUCUUUGUAUCUAUUAUUACACGUGCUGCUGAAGGGAGCAUGGUUUUUAUCUGUGAUACUUAGUUAACAUAUAUAUUACAUUUAUAGCUAUGUAGUAGUUCCCCUAAAUUCUUGUAAAAAUAAAUUUUUAUUUGAUAUUUCAUAUAUGUUUGAAAUGUGAGAAUUCAGAUGUAAUUUUUUACCUUGUUUUGGCAUCUUUGUAUGUUACUUUAAAGAGGAUGUGUGUUCUAAAGGAGGACAUGAGCUGUGUGUUUUCAAGAGAACAAUAGAGUGCGUGUCUUGGGGAAACAUAAUAAAAAUGAACUUUUCUCACCUUCACAGCAACUGUGA